CUAUUAGGGCAUUUUCUUGCAAUAAAUUAUUAGUGGAGAUGAGCGACUGUUGAUGGAGAUGAGUACCUUUAUCAUGCAGAAUAUCAGCAGCCAGAUAUUGGACUUUUCUCACUGCCCCUUAAUUUACUUUUUUAAAUAUUGUCGUUCUAUGGCAAUCAGGCUUUUGGAUAUUGAGGAGGAAGUAAUAACUACAUAAUGUGAUAAUGAUGUCUUUGAGGACCCUUGUCCAUAACAAGCCAUUUGAAUCAGAAUAAUAUCUUGUGCAAUAUGGUGUUAAGGCUUUUAGGUUACAUCUCAUUUCUGAAUGUAUUCUGGAUGACUUCUAUUGACUUUAUGAUGUUUACCUUUCAUAUUUAAAAUAAGAGGGUUCUUUUAGCAGAUUUUGGUUAUAAAACAUCUGAAAUAGUGUAAUUUAAAUAAACAAGGUAAAGGAAAAAAAUAUAUGUAUUAUGCCAAGAAAAUGAGCUAGUCCUUAUGGUUGAGACGAAAUUUUAGCUUUGAGCAUUUUUGUAUGUAAGCACAGAAUGAAGUAGGUUGGAUUUUAUAGGGUUCAUCUCAGUAGGAAUUAUUGUUCUAUUUCAUUUUUGCAGAAUUGAGAAGCCAUCAUAAUUGUUUUAUAUUUAAACUUUUAAACAGAAACCUAAAUUUGCAUAAAAACUCAAGACAGCGUUUACAGUUUCAAGGCAUUUUGUUUGCCUUAUUGUAUUUGUGUACUUCUUCCAUAGUGCCUGGCAAACAGUAAGUGCCAAGUACAUUUAGUUUGAUUUUAUUUUUUAUUGUAUCUUAUUUCUUCUUUUUUGAGGUAGGGUCUUCCUCUGUUGCCCAGGCUGGAGUACAGUGGUGUGAUCAUAGCUCACUGCAGACUUGACCUCCUGGUUGGGGAGUGGUGGUGUGCACCAGUGGUCCCAGCUACUCAGGAGGCUGAAGCAGAAGGACCCCCCCAGCCCGGGAGGCGCUCCAGAACACCCCAGCUUGGGUGACAGAGUUUUCCAACCUAUUGGUGGUAUGUCUGACAGUGGAUCACAACUUGGUUCAAUGGGUAGCCUCACCAUGAAAUCACAGCUUCAGAUCACUGUCAUCUCAGCAAAACUUAAGGAAAAUAAGAAGAAUUGGUUUGGACCAAGUCCUUACGUAGAGGUCACAGUAGAUGGACAGUCAAAGAAGACAGAAAAAUGCAACAACACAAACAGUCCCAAGUGGAAGCAACCCCUUACAGUUAUCGUUACCCCUGUGAGUAAAUUACAUUUUCGUGUGUGGAGUCACCAGACACUGAAAUCUGAUGUUUUGUUGGGAACUGCUGCAUUAGAUAUUUAUGAAACAUUAAAGUCAAACAAUAUGAAACUUGAAGAAGUAGUUGUGACUUUGCAGCUUGGAGGUGACAAAGAGCCAACAGAGACAAUAGGAGACUUGUCAAUUUGUCUUGAUGGGCUACAGUUAGAGUCUGAAGUUGUUACCAAUGGUGAAACUACAUGUUCAGAAAAUGGGGUUUCGCUCUGUUUGCCCAGGCUGGAGUGCAAUAGUGCGAUCUCGGCUCACUGCAACCUCUGCCUCCCGGGUUUAAGUGAUUCUCCUAUCUCAGCCUCCCGAGUAGCUGGGUUUACAGGUGCUUCUCAGAAUGAUGAUGGCUCCAGAUCCAAGGAUGAAACAAGAGUGAGCACAAAUGGAUCAGAUGACCCUGAAGAUGCAGGAGCUGGUGAAAAUAGGAGAGUCAGUGGGAAUAAUUCUCCAUCACUCUCAAAUGGUGGUUUUAAACCUUCUAGACCUCCAAGACCUUCACGACCACCACCACCCACCCCACGUAGACCAGCAUCUGUCAAUGGUUCACCAUCUGCCACUUCUGAAAGUGAUGGGUCUAGUACAGGCUCUCUGCCGCCGACAAAUACAAAUACAAAUACAUCUGAAGGAGCAACAUCUGGAUUAAUAAUUCCUCUUACUAUAUCUGGAGGCUCAGGCCCUAGGCCAUUAAAUCCUGUAACUCAAGCUCCCUUGCCACCUGGUUGGGAGCAGAGAGUGGACCAGCACGGGCGAGUUUACUAUGUAGAUCAUGUUGAGAAAAGAACAACAUGGGAUAGACCAGAACCUCUACCUCCUGGCUGGGAACGGCGGGUUGACAACAUGGGACGUAUUUAUUAUGUUGACCAUUUCACAAGAACAACAACGUGGCAGAGGCCAACACUGGAAUCCGUCCGGAACUAUGAACAAUGGCAGCUACAGCGUAGUCAGCUUCAAGGAGCAAUGCAGCAGUUUAACCAGAGAUUCAUUUAUGGGAAUCAAGAUUUAUUUGCUACAUCACAAAGUAAAGAAUUUGAUCCUCUUGGUCCAUUGCCACCUGGAUGGGAGAAGAGAACAGACAGCAAUGGCAGAGUAUAUUUCGUCAACCACAACACACGAAUUACACAAUGGGAAGACCCCAGAAGUCAAGGUCAAUUAAAUGAAAAGCCCUUACCUGAAGGUUGGGAAAUGAGAUUCACAGUGGAUGGAAUUCCAUAUUUUGUGGACCACAAUAGAAGAACUACCACCUAUAUAGAUCCCCGCACAGGAAAAUCUGCCCUAGACAAUGGACCUCAGAUAGCCUAUGUUCGGGACUUCAAAGCAAAGGUUCAGUAUUUCCGGUUCUGGUGUCAGCAACUGGCCAUGCCACAGCACAUAAAGAUUACAGUGACAAGAAAAACAUUGUUUGAGGAUUCCUUUCAACAGAUAAUGAGCUUCAGUCCCCAAGAUCUGCGAAGACGUUUGUGGGUGAUUUUUCCAGGAGAAGAAGGUUUAGAUUAUGGAGGUGUAGCAAGAGAAUGGUUCUUUCUUUUGUCACAUGAAGUGUUGAACCCAAUGUAUUGCCUGUUUGAAUAUGCAGGGAAGGAUAACUACUGCUUGCAGAUAAACCCCGCUUCUUACAUCAAUCCAGAUCACCUGAAAUAUUUUCGUUUUAUUGGCAGAUUUAUUGCCAUGGCUCUGUUCCAUGGGAAAUUCAUAGACACGGGUUUUUCUUUACCAUUCUAUAAGCGUAUCUUGAACAAACCAGUUGGACUCAAGGAUUUAGAAUCUAUUGAUCCAGAAUUUUACAAUUCUCUCAUCUGGGUUAAGGAAAACAAUAUUGAGGAAUGUGAUUUGGAAAUGUACUUCUCCGUUGACAAAGAAAUUCUAGGUGAAAUUAAGAGUCAUGAUCUGAAACCUAAUGGUGGCAAUAUUCUUGUAACAGAAGAAAAUAAAGAGGAAUACAUCAGAAUGGUAGCUGAGUGGAGGUUGUCUCGAGGUGUUGAAGAACAGACACAAGCUUUCUUUGAAGGCUUUAAUGAAAUUCUUCCCCAGCAAUAUUUGCAAUACUUUGAUGCAAAGGAAUUAGAGGUCCUUUUAUGUGGAAUGCAAGAGAUUGAUUUGAAUGACUGGCAAAGACAUGCCAUCUACCGUCAUUAUGCAAGGACCAGCAAACAAAUCAUGUGGUUUUGGCAGUUUGUUAAAGAAAUUGAUAAUGAGAAGAGAAUGAGACUUCUGCAGUUUGUUACUGGAACCUGCCGAUUGCCAGUAGGAGGAUUUGCUGAUCUCAUGGGGAGCAAUGGACCACAGAAAUUCUGCAUUGAAAAAGUUGGGAAAGAAAAUUGGCUACCCAGAAGUCAUACCUGUUUUAAUCGCCUGGACCUGCCACCAUACAAGAGCUAUGAGCAACUGAAGGAAAAGCUGUUGUUUGCCAUAGAAGAAACAGAAGGAUUUGGACAAGAGUAACUUCUGAGAACUUGCACCAUGAAUGGGCAAGAACUUAUUUGCAAUGUUUGUCCUUCUCUGCCUGUUGCACAUCUUGUAAAAUUGGACAAUGGCUCUUUAGAGAGUUAUCUGAGUGUAAGUAAAUUAAUGUUCUCAUUUAGAUUUAUCUCCCAGUGAUUUCUACUCAGCGUUUCCAGAAAUCAGGUCUGCAAAUGACUAGUCAGAACCUUGCUUAACAUGAGAUUUUAACACAACAAUGAAAUUUGCCUUGUCUUAUUCCACUAGUUUAUUCCUUUAACAACAAUAUUUUAUGUGUGUCAAAAGUCUCACUUGGGAGUAGUGUUUUUUUCUUUUAGACAUUCUGCAGACAUGCAGGGAAGUCCUUUGGUAACUGCAAUAUACAAGAUUUUCCUAUUAAGCCUCUUGGUAAGAGGCAUUUGUUAAAAGUGCAAGCUUACUCCUGCUUCUGGGGAUGUGAGCAAAAUUCGGGCUUGUGUUCUCCCUCUCAUUUUAGUCUGACUUGACUAUUGUUUUUCCUUUCUGGCGCAUGAAUCCAUACAUCAUUCCUGGAAGUGAGGCAAGACUCUUGCAUCUCUACAAAGUAGUUUUGUCAAUUUGAAUUCAGGGAAAAGUUGGUCACAGCCUGCAAAUGACUUCAUUUGGAAGUCUGAUUGUUUCAGUUGCCUGACAAAUACUACACUUUACAAACAAUGUUAACACUGUGAUUCCUUCAUUGUUUUAAGAAGUUAACCUAGGGCCGGGCAUGGUGGCUCAUACCUGUAAUCCUAGCACUCUGGGAGGCCGAGGCAGGAGGAUCCCUUUAGCCCAGGAGUUAAAGACCAGCCUGGGCAACAUAGGGAGACCCUGUCUUUUUUUUGGGCAGCGUGGUGGGGGAUAAAUAAAUAAAAGGAAAAAAAACUUAGCCUAGAAUUAGAAUUAAUUUAAUUGAAUUCAUCUAAAGAUGUCUCUGGUGAUUUUUAUAUGUUCCGCUAUAUAAUUGAUGCUUUAUAGUUUUAUCAUAAUCCAACAACUUCAGUUAUAUUUAAUUAUUGUUAAGGAGUUUAAGACUAGAAAGACUAGAGUGCUUUCUAGUCCAAAUAGAGGUCAGUGAAACAGCUUUUGACAUCAGAUUUUCAUUUGAGAGGGAGAGCUGUGGUACUGGCUAAAAAGAAAGGAAGAUAACAUCCAGUAACCACAGGAAUAUAUUCUCUGUGAAUUAAAAGUCUUCAAAGUUAUCAUUUCUCUGACAUAUGUUGGAGUAGUCAUUUCCAUUCUUUACAUUGUCAUGAACUGGAUUGAUAACCCUCAUCUGCAAUAUUUUCACCCCUAAAAUUUUUAACAGGGUUUCCUUUUUUUCUCACGACUAUUUAAGUUUAGAUUGCUCCAUUAUUAACUGAUUAAUGCACUUUGAAGUUCUCUGGAAUUAAUUAUUUUAACUUGGCCUAGCUUCGACUGUCAAGGUGGCUGUUAUAAAUUUGACUUCAUUGGCAGUGGAUGAAGCCUAAGCCAGCUGAGUCUCUAUCAUAGCUGAACCCUGAGGACAGCCUCAUAGCUCAUGUAUCAGGGACUUUUGCCACAUUUCAGAGGCAUAGCAUGAACAAGUAAUAUUAAGCCAAGAAUAAGCAGCAGAACCCUGUUCCAUAUGGAAAAAAGAAAAACAAUUUUUUGUCCCUAAUGUUCUUCCUUUUACAUCCUGGAACAACAAUAAAAACAUUUUUUUAAACUUGUCUACUGUAAGAUACUGCCAUCAUAAAGCAGAGACUUACAUGAGUGAAAGGGUUGCCUCAUCAAGCAGCUCAGUGUAAAUGGGGAGGCUAGGCUCUCCCCAGCCCUAUGGUUUUUUUAUUUCAUGUACCCCAGGAAAUACUGUGUGGUUUCUAAAAGCCCUGGUUGUUAAAAGUAGGGACUCUGCCUUUUUGUUGGUAGGGAGAAAAAACGCUAUUGCUUUGUCUUACAGAGCGAAUGUCUGCCAACUACCCGUUCAUUAUAUAAGUCUGAACUUGGUAAUAUAUGGCUAAUGAAGAUUAAGCCCUCUAUAAAGACUUCCUGUUGAGGUGAAUUCUCAUACUGAAAUGUAGUUACCUACAAUAUUUACUAGAGAUUUAUGAAAUUAAAUUAAGAGAUAAUGUAAGAAAAUACAUUUUUUUGGUUCUAUAUAAUGCUUCAUGAUUCAUUUAGGGACCUAGAAAUAUUGUGUGAAAAUAUAUAAAUAUCACCCAAAAGGCUUUCUGCCCUAUAUUUUUAAAAUACAGAAUAGUUAUAUUUGAAGUAGCCCUGGCCCUAGUUCUAUAGGGCUUGGCUAUUUAAUAUUUUUAUGGAAGAAGUGUUUAGUUCUGGAAAAGGUAAAUGCUUGUAUAUAUUUUUGCAGCCUGGGAUCUCCCUACUCCAUUUUUUCCUUUAAUUUAAGUGGCCACAUGUAUAUGUCUUCCCUGCUGUGUUAGGAAAAUGGGGGCUGGAUAUCCCAAGAAUCAGAGGUUAUAUAAAAAUACUGCAAAUAGACCGCAGACAUAAAUAUCUACCAAAUGCUAUCUUAAAUUUUGGUCCAAACUGAACAUAUGGAAAUAGAUUUAUUGUAAGUAUUUACUUAGAGCUUUUUCUUAAAUCUGAACUAACUUGCUUUUAGAAGUCUUUUUCUUUGUAAGCAUUGUAAAUGCUAAUAAAUCCUGUUAAUUUUUUUUUUUUUUUUUUUUUUUUUUUACUGCAUGUUACAUUGAAAUAAAAACAAAGUAAAAUGAGCAAUUGCCUUAUUGUUCUGCUCUUUUGCAGGGGGUGGGGGUUGGGGAAGACAGCAUUCCACAGCCUGGUCAGGAGGGAAGGACCUCACUUGUUUCAUCAAAUGGAGUGGUUUAAAACUGAUCAAGCAGCUCAUAAUAAUGAAUUCCUGCUCUGUCUUUUAUUAUCUUAUGUCAGAGUGCAGCAAAAUCUCAUUUCAUAAGACUUACAAUAACUCUAUUUAAAAUUCAGGUAUUGUACUCGGGAGGCUGAGGUGGGAGGAUCCCAGGAGUUCAAAUCCUGCCUGGGCAACAUAGCAAGACCCUGUCUCUUAAAAAAACAAAAAGACAUAUUCAGGUACUGAUUUUUCAUCAAGAGAUUGACAUACCAAUGAUCAGAAAUUUUAGUGAAACUUGACUCAACUAUACACAAAGUUCUCAUCCUAAAUGAACUAUUUCAGUCAAGCCCACUCUACCACUUUUUACUUAUCUGGUUAAUAAUCCGAAAUGUUACCGGGGUUGACUCACGGAAUUAAAUUUUUCCUCUAUUUUUAUAUCCUUUCCUGUUGUGGAUGUAACUUACCUUUCUAAACUCCUUUAGAGUUAACGACUUCUAUUUAGUAUUGUUGGUAUCUCCAGCCCCCCUCCUUUUUUUGUUUUUCUUUUAGUUAUUUACUUUGUUUGUAUAAUUUGCUUUCAUUAACUAAAAAUGGAAUUGGCAGCACUGGAUUGUAUAUUACUGUAUUAAGAGUACCUUUGUUUUCUUGAUCUGUUACUUUUAAUACUCAGGUAAUGCUACAAAUAUUACAGGGAGUCAAAUGCUUUUAUAAAGUUCCUUCAGUGGUUGCCUCACUUGCGUUUUCCUACAAGAUGUAAGACUGUUUAUAAUUAAACUUUUUUGGUCCUUCAUUUGCAUGCUUUUCUAUCAGUCUUGGGUAAGGAGGGGUCUCUUUCCUCUCUCCCCGGCCCCACCUUCUGAGACUUAUAUGUGACCAGGUCACAUAGAUUUCUGCCUCUCUGCUUUUUUAAGUGGCAAGUUACAGCCCAUCUGGAUUGUGGUAUUGUUCCCAGACCAAAUCAAGGGUUGGACUGCUUAUUCUCGCAGCCCAAUAAUGAGGUGCAGAUGAACUGAGAAAGGAGGGAGUUUAUUUCUGUAACCAGGUAUGGGGAGAAAGCCUGGAAAUGAUCCCAAGACCAACUCAAAACUACAAAGUUUUCCAGAGCUUAUUUACAUUAUAAGCUAUAUGUCUACAUGUGAGUGUACAUUCAUCUAAAGACAUAAGUGAUUC